AAUCUAAAGUUUUUCACCUCUCUCUAGUAAGACAUCUGAAACUCAUAAGCCAUCUUUAAGAAUUUCUUACAAAAACAUGCUGGAAGACAGUGGAUCUUGUUUGUAUCCUGAAGAUUUUUUUCUCUUCGUUAUUUUAAAUUAAUUGUCAACAGAUGUGCAACUGUUAGGUUGGUUCUUAAGUCACUCGGAGAAGAGAGAGAUGCAUCUACUCAAGGUUGGCACUUGGAGAAACAACACUGCCUCUUCCUGGCUUAUGAAGUUCAGUGUUCUUUGGCUUGUUAGUCAGAACUGUUGCAGAGCAAGUGUUGUUUGGAUGGCUUAUAUGAACAUAUCAUUUCAUGUUGGGAAUCAUGUGUUGUCAGAGUUGGGAGAGACUGGAGUCUUUGGAAGAAGCUCCACUUUGAAGAGAGUGGCAGGAGUUAUAGUGCCACCAGAGGGAAAAAUCCAAAAUGCAUGUAAUCCCAAUACCAUUUUCAGCCGAUCAAAGUACUCAGAGACCUGGCUUGCACUUAUUGAACGGGGAGGUUGUACCUUCACACAGAAAAUUAAAGUGGCAACUGAGAAGGGAGCCAGUGGAGUGAUCAUCUAUAACGUUCCAGGUACUGGCAACCAGGUGUUCCCCAUGUUUCAUCAGGCAUUUGAAGAUGUCGUUGUGGUUAUGAUUGGUAACUUAAAAGGCACGGAAAUUUUCCAUUUAAUUAAGAAGGGAGUUCUCAUUACAGCCGUGGUUGAGGUGGGGAGAAAGCACAUCAUCUGGAUGAAUCACUAUUUGGUCUCUUUUGUGAUUGUCACAACUGCUACCUUAGCAUAUUUCAUCUUUUAUCACAUUCAUAGACUUUGUUUAGCAAGGAUUCAGAACCGGAGAUGGCAGCGAUUAACAACAGAUCUUCAGAACACAUUUGGACAACUCCAACUUCGAGUAGUAAAAGAGGGGGAUGAAGAAAUAAAUCCAAAUGGGGAUAGCUGCGUAAUUUGCUUUGAACGCUAUAAGCCUAAUGACAUAGUUCGUAUUCUGACUUGUAAACAUUUUUUCCACAAGAAUUGCAUUGACCCCUGGAUUUUACCCCAUGGGACAUGCCCCAUUUGCAAAUGUGAUAUUCUUAAAGUUUUGGGGAUUCAAGUGGUUGUUGAAAAUGGAACAGAACCUUUGCAAGUUCUAAUGUCAAAUGAACUGCCUGAAACCUUAUCACCUAGUGAAGAGGAGACAAAUAAUGAAGUUUCUCCUGCAGGAACCUCAGAUAAAGUAAUCCAUGUGGAGGAGAACCCUACUUCUCAGAAUAAUGACAUCCAGCCUCAUUCAGUAGUGGAAGAUGUUCAUCCUUCACCUUGAUGGCAUGACUUUUGAGGAAGUGUAUUAAACCUGUAUGUGAAAUCAGGUCCUAA